CCAGAUUGAAGUGAUCCUCCUGCCUCAGCCUCCUGGGUCACCGGGAUUACAGGUGUCCACCACCACGCCCAGCCUAGUCUGACCAAUUGUGUAGGUCACCCGAAUAUUCAGUUUUGCUCCGAGAGGUGGAGACGGACCCCAGUCAUUCAGUGAAGUGGAUGGCAGAGCUUCACCUCCAGCUAAGUAGCCACAUUUUCUGGCAACAAAUAACCUUUUUUUUUUUUUUUUUUUUUUUUUUUUUUGGAGACGGAGCCUCACUCUGUCACCCGGGCUGGAGUGCAGUGGCACGAUCUCGGCUCACUGCAACCUCUGCCACCCGGGUUCAAGCGAUUCUCCAGGUUCAAGCCUUAGCCUCCUGAGUAGCUCGUACUGCAGGCACCCACCACCAUGCCUGGCUAAUUUUUUGUAUUUUUAGUAGAAACAGGGUUUCACCAUGUUGGGCAGGCUGGUCUGGAACUCCUGACCUCAAGUGAUCCACCCGCCUCAUCCUCCUGAAGUGCUGGGAUUACGGAUGUGAGGCACCGCGCCCGGCCUGGCCACAAAUAAUCUAAUUAUGUCACUGCCCCUGAAAAUCGGUCACCAAAGGGUCUCAUAGCCCCAGGCCCCAAGGCCUCCCCGCUGAGUGUGCCAUCAAACACUGCAGCCUUAAAAACCCAUGGACCCCAGAUGCCCCCAGUCCUGUCCACCCCUUUCAGCGUCCUGAAGCUUGUUCCGUGGCUCCCACUGCCUGAAAUCAGCCCAUCGCCCCCAUCGAAGUCCUUCAUGCUCCAUUCCCCUUUCUUGGUUCCCUCCGCCUUGGGAGCUGGGGACGUCUAGGUCCGGUUCCGUGUCCCACGCUUUGGAGCAGUAGAACCAACGCGCGGCCAGCGCAUCUUCUGCCACCAGAGGGCGCCCGCGCCUCGGGCUUUGGCUCCCACACCGCGGCCCGCCAGGCCUCGAUUCAACCCGCGCGUCGCACGGUGAAACUGAGGGCAUCCCCAGCUCAAGGCUGCAGACGCUACUCGGGGCACCGCGGAGGCAGCCGCCCUGGAGCGGGAGCUGCUGGAGGAUUAUCGCUUUGGGCGGCAGCAGCUCGUGGAGCUGUGCGGUCAUGCUAGUGCCGUGGCUGUGACCAAGGUGGGGAAACUGAAGCUCAGAGGUGGCGAGGGGCCUGCCCUGGGUCAGAGGGGGAUGGAAGCAGAGCUGCAACCCAGGUGUGUCUGGCUCUGGAGUAAACCCCCACACCUCGAGGGGCCAGGAGGAUGACACAAGGGUGAUAGCAAUAAUCAUACUAUGGAGUGCUUCACCGUGCAGCCAGCAGUGCUGGGCAUCAGUUUCCUCUGCAACAGCAUAAUAAAUGGCGUUCCCGUUGCCCGCUCUCUCCCGGAAGCAGAGGACGGUGCUGGUCGUGUGUGGCCCGGAGCAGAACGGGGCAGUGGGGCUGGUCUGUGCCCGGCACCUGCGGGUGUUUGAGUAUGAACCCACCAUCUUCUACCCCACACGCUCGCUGGACCUGCUGCAUCGGGACCUGACCACCCAGUGCGAGAAGAUGGACAUCCCCUUCCUGAGCUACCUGCCCACUGAGGUGCAGCUCAUUAACGAAGCCUAUGGGCUGGUGGUGGAUGCCGUACUGGGCCCCGGCGUGGAGCCGGGCGAGGUCGGGGGCCCCUGCACCCGCGCGCUGGCCACGCUCAAGCUGCUGUCCAUCCCCCUCGUGAGCCUGGACAUCCCCUCAGGCUGGGACGCAGAGACCGGCAGCGAUUCGGAGGACGGGCUGCGGCCUGACGUGCUGGUGUCUCUCGCGGCGCCCAAGCGCUGCGCUGGCCGCUUCUCCGGGCGCCACCACUUCGUGGCCGGCAGGUUCGUGCCCGAUGACGUGCGCCGCAAGUUCGCUCUGCGCCUGCCGGGAUACACGGGCACCGACUGCGUCGCGGCACUGUGACCGCCACCCGCGGCCACACCGCAGGGACCCUCGCCAAUAAACAGCCCUCCCACCACC